AGUUGCUGUGGAAACCCCACGGGCAGGAGGCCCCCGGCCAGCACAUCCUGUCUGCUUGUGUCUGCUGCAGAGUUCUGGGACCGGGGCCAUGUCUCCACACCUCACUGCUCUCCUGGGCCUAGUGCUCUGCCUGGCCCAGACCAUCCACACGCAGGAGGGGGCCCUUCCCAGACCCUCCAUCUCGGCUGAGCCAGGCACUGUGAUCUCCCCGGGGAGCCAUGUGACUUUCAUGUGCCGGGGCCCGGUUGGGGUUCAAACAUUCCGCCUGGAGAGGGAGGAUAGAGCCAAGUACAAAGAUAGUUAUAAUGUGUUUCGACUUGGUCCAUCUGAGUCAGAGGCCAGAUUCCACAUUGACUCAGUAAGUGAAGGAAAUGCCGGGCUUUAUCGCUGCCUCUAUUAUAAGCCCCCUGGAUGGUCUGAGCACAGUGACUUCCUGGAGCUGCUGGUGAAAGAAAGCUCUGGAGGCCCGGACUCCCCGGACACAGAGCCCGGCUCCUCAGCUGGUCAGUAGCAGGGCCCUCAGCUGGAGGGGAUUACAGGGGAAUCUGUGCUGCGGAUGCUGUUCCGGGUCCAGCCCUCUGCCCUGGGCUUGGAGUCAAGGUCUAGGGAGGCCACGGGAAGGCACCGACACCCACCAAGCUCUGGGAGGUCGCUAAUGCUCACAGAGACCAUAGCAGCAAUGGUACCGUGAUUGCAACCUUGUUCCAUGCCAGGAACUGUGGAAAGCACUUAAUGCAAGCACCACUUAAUGGGGGAGGUACUAGUCUGAUCCUCUAACUCCUCCUCCUCUCUAAUAUGCAAAACAUAAAUUAAAGUUUCGUGCUUAACGGCACAAGGCCAUGAAGGGGCAGGGGCCACCCACCCGGGCAGCCCCACCCCAGACUUCCGGGCUCGCCCGAGCUCCACGCUGCCCCCUUGUGGGCGUGGCCUCACCAUUCACCCCGCUCUGCACCUGAUGGAGGGACUUAGAACUCACCUUCCAACCUGGGACACCCGGAGAGGGACGGGGCUGCUCCUGUUGGCUCUGUGAUCUCCGGGGGAGGCCUGAACGGUGGAGUAAGGUCCCUUAAGAGGAGGAGGGCUCCACAGGGAGGGGACGUAGCUGUGAACGGUGACCAGGAUGAAGCCAUGAGGCUUCCCUUCCAUCUGGCUCUGCCCUGGACUCUGUGAUGGGAGAGAAGCUGCCUCUGGCUCUGCCCCUGGACUCUGUGUGAUGGGAGUGAAGCUGCCCCAAGUCCCUGGGUCUCAAGUUGUCCAUCUCCGCCUGUGAUCUGUGACCAGAAACUGCCAGGGGAGGACACGGGGUCAUAAGCCAUUCGCGGCCCCUUCCCCACCUGGGUUUCUAUCCCCAGAGUACGUCCUUGGACCUAGACCCGGUGACUGCCUGUGAGGCUCGGGCUGUGAGCUCAGGCAGGUGGGACCAGGGGCUGAAGCCACAUGGGGAGGUGGGAGGAGCGAUGCCGUGCUCCAUCCGGACCCCCUCAGAGGCUCCUGGGCUGCUGGGGCACAGCGGGACAUGCUCCUGAGUCCCGCAGACCUGGUUCAAGUCCAGUGUCUGGUUUUUAUUAGCCUUCUGUCUGCGGGAAUAUCUUGCCUCUGUUUCUCUCCCUCUCUUCUUCUCCUUCCUUCUCUCUUCUCUCACCUUCAUGCAGUGACAUAUAAAGGUCACGAGGGCAGACCCUCCUGCAGCCAGAUU